AGAGCUGCAUGGGGAGACGCCGCUGCAGGUCCGGUUUCUCGGUGUCUGGUCGGUGCCAUCAUUUUCCUGCCCCUCCCCCGUCCUCCCCAAGCUGGCCACUUCCCCUCCCCCUCCCCCUCCCCACCGAGGGGGCAGGGGGCUGGGCACGGAGUCUCUAUGAUGAUGCCAUGUGCGGUGUCUGUGCCGGGCGGCAGGGACUGGGGCGGCAGCGAGAGGAGGCAGUGGAGCCAGGAGAGCGGUGGUGACCGCUGACCGCUUGCCCGGCUGCUCCUCCGCUCCCUCCCGCCCACCUCCUUCCUUUGGGGCUGGUACUCAGACCCACCCCCACCCCCUCCCCGCCUCCUCGGGCCCUCCCAGCCUCUCACGUAAGCCUCCCCUCCCCACCUGCCUGGUGGCUCCCUCCCCUCCCCCAUCCGCAUCCUCCUCCUCCUGUCCCCUCUUCCUCUCUGUCCCUCACCAAGCCAUCCCCUCUUUGCCUCUCCCCAUCCCUCGCUGGCCUGCUCCUGCUCCCCUUCUCCCAUCCUCCCCUCCCCCGUCUCUGCCCAGCCAGCCCCCUCCCGACUCCCCAGUUUCAUCGGACUCCCUGGCCCCAUCCCGUCCCCGCCCUGGCCCCUUUGUGCCCCUUCUCAUCGUUUUCUCCCUCCUUCCCGGGCUUGGCGUCCCUUCUCCACCCCUAACUCCUUCCACUCGGCCUCCCUGCCCCUUCACGGCCCGCCUGCCUCCCUGCCCAAGUCCUGAGCCACCAUGCUGACCCCGAUGGUGGCCGGGGGGGUGGUGUUCCCCGGACUCUUCCUCCUCUCCAAGAACACGCUCCAGCGGCUGCCCCAGCUACGCUGGGAGGAGGCCGACGCAGUCAUUGUCUCAGCCAGGGCCAGCAUGCGGCGAAGACAUUCCUAUAAGACAUUAGGGACUGAGGCCAGGGCCAGACAGCUAGGUGUCAUUCAGGGCUGGUGUCCUCUGUCCAGGCCAUCAUGGCCUCCACUGCCGGCUACAUCGUCUCCACCUCCUGCAAGCACAUCAUUGAUGACCAACACUGGCUGUCCUCUGCCUACACGCAAUUUGCUGUGCCCUACUUCAUCUACGACAUCUACGCCAUGUUCCUCUGUCACUGGCACAAGCACCAGGUCAAAGGGCAUGGAGGGGACGACGGAGCGGCCAGAGCCCCGGGCAGCACGUGGGCCAUAGCGCGUGGCUACCUGCACAAGGAGUUCCUCAUGGUGCUCCACCAUGCCGCCAUGGUGCUGGUGUGCUUCCCACUCUCAGUGGUGUGGCGACAGGGUAAGGGAGACUUCUUUCUGGGUUGCAUGUUGAUGGCAGAGGUCAGCACGCCCUUCGUCUGCCUUGGCAAGAUCCUCAUCCAGUACAAGCAGCAGCACACACUGCUGCACAAGGUGAACGGGGCCCUGAUGCUGCUCAGCUUCCUCUGCUGCCGGGUGCUGCUCUUUCCCUACCUGUACUGGGCCUACGGGCGCCAUGCCGGCCUGCCCCUGCUGGCCGUGCCCCUGGCCAUCCCUGCCCACGUCAACCUGGGCGCUGCGCUGCUCCUGGCCCCUCAGCUCUACUGGUUCUUCCUCAUCUGCCGUGGGGCCUGCCGCCUCUUCUGGCCCCGCUCCCGGCCGCCCCCGGCCUGCCAGGCCCAGGACUGAGGCCGGGGGCCGGGACCCUCCCCCUCCCCACCCCCACCCCCGUGGAGACAGGGCUCUGGGGCUGAUGGCUGGGGUUGGGAGCCAGGGUCCUCUUGCCCGGACAACCCCAGGACUGACGAUGACCCCGAAAGGGAAGAGGCCCCAUCUCUCGGGGACUGAGGGGGUGGAGAGAGGGGACCUCUUCCCCCUACUCUGCCCCCUUCCUGCACACCCUUGCGCUGGAGGAGGGGAGGGGGCACCGCCUCCCACCCACUGAGGGCAGGAGGGCUUGUGGGGAGGGACACCAACAGGGUUUCAAGGGGACCAGGAGUCAGAAUGUGGGGAGACGCCUCUGCCAAGGCCAUCCCAGCCCCUAUGCUGCCAUCCCCCAGGGCUCCCCAUCACCCGAGAGGAGAGGACGCCCCAACUAACCCCCGCUGGCCCUCGGGCCUCCCGAGUGGCCGGCUGCAACCACGGCUCCUCUCCAGGGUAGGCCAGCUUGAGGAAUCUUAUUUAUUUUAUUUAUUUACCCAAAUUUGAACUAGUCUGUUGGGUUGGGGGAAGGAGGUGGCUGCUACCCCCAAGCCUUCCCAGUGCUGACAACCCCGGGGGCAGGCGAGGGCGCCCAGUCCCUCACCAUCGGCUGCACAUCGCGCCCUCGGGCCCUGCCAUGUCCCUGGUGCUACUGACCUCUCAAGGCUUCCUCCAAUCUGGGGUCGGGGGACCCUGGGAGGUGCUUUACAGACCGCUAAUAAAAGACGAUCUGCGUGAACGCCA